AACCACUUCCGGCGCAAGUGGCUUCUGAUAAUCAUGGCGCCCCUCGGAACAACUGUAUUGCUGUGGAGCCUCUUGAGGAGUUCUCCGGGCGUGGAACGGGUCUGUUUCCGGGCUCGAAUCCAGCCCUGGCACGGUGGCCUGCUCCAACCGCUACCUUGCUCUUUCGAGAUGGGGCUGCCACGCCGCCGGUUCAGCUCCGAGGCCGAAUCUGGUAGCCCAGAGACCAAGAAACCUACAUUUAUGGAUGAGGAAGUUCAAAGCAUACUCACGAAAAUGACAGGCUUGAACUUGCAGAAGACUUUUAAGCCAGCUAUACAAGAACUGAAGCCACCAACCUAUAAGCUAAUGACUCAGGCACAGUUGGAAGAGGCUACAAGACAGGCAGUUGAGGCAGCUAAAGUACGAUUAAAAAUGCCACCAGUUCUGGAAGAGCGAGUACCAAUAAAUGAUGUGUUAGCUGAAGAUAAGAUUUUGGAAGGAACAGAAACAACCAAAUAUGUGUUUACUGAUAUAUCAUAUAGCAUACCACACCGGGAGCGUUUUAUUGUCGUCAGAGAACCAAGUGGCACACUACGCAAAGCCUCUUGGGAAGAACGGGACCGAAUGAUACAAGUUUAUUUCCCAAAAGAAGGUCGUAAAAUUUUGACACCAAUAAUUUUCAAGGAAGAAAAUCUUAGGACUAUGUAUAGCCAGGACAGGCAUGUUGAUGUCCUCAAUCUCUGCUUUGCCCAGUUUGAGCCAGAUUCCACAGAGUAUAUCAAGGUUCAUCACAAGACCUAUGAAGAUAUAGAUAAACGUGGAAAAUAUGACCUUUUACGUUCAACAAGAUACUUUGGUGGAAUGGUGUGGUAUUUUGUAAAUAAUAAAAAGAUUGAUGGUUUGCUGAUUGACCAGAUUCAGAGAGAUUUAAUCGAUGAUGCAACCAACUUGGUCCAGCUGUAUCACGUGCUCCAUCCAGAUGGCCAGUCGGCUCAAGGGGCCAAGGAUCAGGCUGCUGAGGGAAUAAAUUUAAUCAAGGUCUUUGCAAAAACAGAAGCACAGAAGGGAGCCUAUAUAGAACUAACACUGCAGACUUAUCAAGAAGCACUCAGUCGCCAUUCUGCAGCUUCCUAAAAAUAUUUUAAAAAUACAUUUAUUUUACUAAAUACUGACUACAUUUCUCUGUUAAUAUUGAGCUAAAUGUUAAAAAAUGGCCAGAUUAAAAGAUAUCAAUUUGUAGUUCUCCCUACAAAGCAAAAA